ACUCUCUUUACAGUCAGCCUUCUGCUUGCCACAGUCAUAGUGGGCAGUCAGUGAAUCUUCCCCAAGUGCUGACAAUUAAUACCUGGUUUAGCGGCAAAGAUUCAGAGAGGCGUGAGCAGCCCCUCUGGCCUUCAGGUAGGUCUGAUACCUUCAUUUCUACCAAAGCUAAAAAAUGGGAGCCUAUGUUAGUAAACUUUAAGGGAAUGAAGAUGCCACAUUUUGGCAGUGUGUUAGUCACAAGUGGAUUUGGUGUCUAGAUAGGGAAGGGAUGAGUAGAAUUUGGAAAAUGUGGGGCUUUCUGUUCUCUGGCUGCUUCAGGGAUUUAAUUAUUAGGCCUUUAGAGCACUAUUAUUAAUCUUCGUACAUAAAUCGUUCUCUGGCCUAAGACAGGAAGGAAGACCUAAUCCUGGUUUUACUGCCAGCAGAAAUAAAAUAAUAUAUGCCUCAAACCUGAUUAACAGUGCAAGAUACUGUUAUUCACACAUUAAAUGCCUGAAGUUACUUACAUGAGGUUACUUGCUACUCUGGAGCAAUCAAGAAAACAUGGCCAGCACGGAUCAGCAAGAUUUAAUGUUUCACAGUACAGUAUCUUUCUUUGGAAAAGAAAAAGUCAGUUCAGAUAUUAGGAACUAUAAACCCAGACCUCAUACUAUGAGUCCUUUCAUUAUACUCAACUAUGCCCUAGCAUCAGAGAGAAUAAAUGAAAAUCUCCCUGCUGAAGAAUGUUAGCAUGGGGUUGGGAAAAUUGUAUAUAUUUAUUGGUCCUAUAUUUCUGUCCUUUACAAAGAAUCUUUAAUGUGUUGACCUUGAAGCCUCCCUCAGCUGAAGAACAGGAUCUUAUUCUUUUAAAUCUGCCUGUUUUUAUGUAGCCUAUUAAAAGGAAAAGACUUCAGUAGGUUAUUUUAGAUAUAGUAUAAUCAUUUAAAAACUCUUUUUAAAAACCAAGGUGUGACUAAUACAGUCAUAUUGAAACUAUGGAAGAGAUACAAUGGUCUACUCCAGUGAAAAAUAUAUUCAAGUUGAUAAAGCAAAAUUUCAAAAACCAAAUGUGGCAAAAUCAUGUGAAAACACUUUCAAUGUUCCUGUUUAUUCUUUAAAUGCAUACAUCAUCUGGUUAAAGUGAGUAAUCUAAAAAUUAAUUACUCACACUUGAACCAUGUUACAAGAGGAGGUAAUUCAUCUUAGCAAUAAGAAACUUUACCACUGUUUUUAGGGCCUUGAAAUUAUGAAAUGAGCCAAAAGCAGAGCAUCAAAGGGAAAACAGGUCAAAAGCCCUGUUUCAAAAAUCUUUAGGGGCCUAGACUAAGCUACAAAAAUGGACAAUCCUCCUUAUGUCUUGCCCAAGAAAAUGUUUCUGUGUAAUCUACAAUAAUCAUGUUUUCACUUACGAGAAGCCACAAUUCCUACAGCAACCUUAAAAUGAAACCAAGAGGCGACAAUAAAAACAUUGCUUUAAAACAACUGUUCUUGAAAAAUCCCUUUGGAUCUGGAAUCCAUUACCACUGUAUGGCUUGCCUUGUAUCUCAAUAACAGUCAUCACAGGUGUUUGAAACAAGCAGGCCUUGGCUUUGGUGUUCCCCCCACCCAAAAUGGGACAACUCUCUGAUCAUAAUCACUCAGGCUGAGUGUAAUCACCUACAGUUUUCUGAAGUGAGGGUCAAUAAUGUCUCCUUUUAGUUUCUAUGAAUAGCAUUUUUCAUAGUUGCUCAGAUGCCUUCCCUCAUGUAGGCUUGGGUAGGCCAUGAUAUAAAUAAAACACUGCCUAGAUUAUUUUAUAAGCAGGGCAGUUUGCUGAAUAUACAACUGAGGGAGACAGGCUUGUUUUCAUAACUUUGAUAAUAAUCCUUCUGAGACACCAUUUCCUCACCUGCUUUAAUAACCCACCAGAUAAUUGUUGAAAGAUCACCCCCUUACGAGUCUCCCAAGUAGACUGAAAAUAAUAACUACAAGAGAUUAUUUAGCAGUAAAUUACAGCUGAUCUACAGAAGUUCUUUAAAGCAAAAAAAAAAAAAAACAAAAAAAAAACACUACCAUCUCAUUAGAGUGACCAGAGAUUCUAAAUAGUCCAAGGAAUCUUUGCAGGAGGAAUAAAGAUAAAUUAGAUAAAUUAUAGUAUCAAUUAACAUUUAUUGAGUGUUUAUGUGCCAGGCACUGUUCUAUGUGAUUUACACGUGCUAUCCCAUUUAUUUCUCAAAACAGCCCAGUGAAUAUAUACCAAGAUUAUCCCCAGUUAGACAAAGGGUGACAAGAAGAAUAAAAUAUUAACUAUCUUCUGUUAAUAAAUUAACUACUACCAGCACCCUCAUCAUAUAUGUUUAUCCAAUUCUUUUAGUUCAAAUGUUUAUCUGUCUAUACCCACUGACCUGAUUCCCAUAUCCUAAAGCCCCUUCUCAUCCUCUCCAACCUUAUCAACUGCCAUUACUGGCAGGUGCGUAUGCACUAGACCUUAUUUUUGGUAAAUUUUAAAAUAAUCAUAACUAUCGUCUACUAUAUGCAAAUCCCUGUUCUAAGUACUUUACGUAUAUUCAACUAUUAAUCAUAACUGACAUCAAUAUAUGAGGUUGGUAAAAUUAUUAUCUCAGUUUUCAGAUGAGGAAACUGAGGCACACAGAGGUUACAUAACUUGCCCAAAGUCAUGUAGUUAGUGGCAGAGCCAGGAUUUGAAUCCAGCCAGUAAGCAUUCAGAGUCCACACUCAGCCAUUGUUUAUACUGCUUUUGAAGCAUAUUAAGAAUUAACUCUUAAAAGUCAAGAAAUCUGUGCUAUGUUUUGUUUCCUUUAACAUUUGGUGCACAGGACAUCACACUGCAAACACGGAGUGUAUUCCACAACUCUCUAAGGUAAACAAUAAUAAAAUAGAAAUUUAUCAAGCUUCCUUCAUCUAGUAAAUAUUCUUUUUGUUGUAACACAAGUAUGAAAUUCUGAAUAAUUCAAACACUUCUAUGCUUAGUCCCUGCUUACUUACUACAGAAUUAUUAAAGAAUUACCCAAAAGUUCUUGGACUGGAAAGAUGUGAAAAAGCCACUAACUCUAUUUUCCUAGAAUGAAGAUGAAAAGAAGAUGUGUUUAGGAACCUUCUCUGCUUCCCUAAAAGAACCCUAAAAACAGGAGUAAAAACAGUGAAGAAAACAAAGGACCUUCAAAGUGCACUCGUUAAAACCUAAUAACUGUAUUUCUAUUACUAAAUGUAGAAGUGGUAAACAUCUUUAACAGGCAAUGUCUCCCCUGCACUCUAGGGAUUCAAAGAUCCAUCUUUCGGUUCUGUAAGACAGUCACGGCUUUUGUAACCUCGGUGCCCCCUUCAACCUCCCGCCCCAAGCACCUCCAGGGUCGUCAGGGGUGUAGUUUUGAGUCGCGCUCCUAAGCAUCCAGACAGGCAGGACACCGUAACGACAUCUCUGCCGGGAGUCCCUUCAGACUGCGGUCUCCAGACAAAAAUCUACGUACCAUCAGAAACUAUGUCUCUGCAGAUGGUAACAGUCAGUAAUAACAUAGCCUUAAUUCAGCCAGGCUUCUCACUGAUGAAUUUUGAUGGACAAGUUUUCUUCUUUGGACAAAAAGGCUGGCCCAAAAGAUCCUGCCCCACUGGAGUUUUCCAUCUGGAUGUAAAGCAUAACCAUGUCAAACUGAAGCCUACAAUUUUCUCUAAGGAUUCCUGCUACCUCCCUCCUCUUCGCUACCCAGCCACUUGCACAUUCAAAGGCAGCUUGGAGUCUGAAAAGCAUCAAUACAUCAUCCAUGGAGGGAAAACACCAAACAAUGAGGUUUCAGAUAAGAUUUAUGUCAUGUCUAUUGUUUGCAAGAACAACAAAAAGGUUACUUUUCGCUGCACAGAGAAAGACUUGGUAGGAGAUGUUCCUGAAGCCAGAUAUGGUCAUUCCAUUAAUGUGGUGUACAGCCGAGGGAAAAGUAUGGGUGUUCUCUUUGGAGGACGCUCAUACAUGCCUUCUACCCACAGAACCACAGAAAAAUGGAAUAGUGUAGCUGACUGCCUGCCCUGUGUUUUCCUGGUGGAUUUUGAAUUUGGGUGUGCUACAUCAUACAUUCUUCCAGAACUUCAGGAUGGGCUAUCUUUUCAUGUCUCUAUUGCCAAAAAUGACACCAUCUAUAUUUUAGGAGGACAUUCACUUGCCAAUAAUAUCCGGCCUGCCAACCUGUACAGAAUAAGGGUUGAUCUUCCCCUGGGUAGCCCAGCUGUGAAUUGCACAGUCUUGCCAGGAGGAAUCUCUGUCUCCAGUGCAAUCCUGACUCAAACUAACAAUGAUGAAUUUGUUAUUGUUGGUGGCUAUCAGCUUGAAAAUCAAAAAAGAAUGAUCUGCAACAUCAUCUCUUUAGAGGACAACAAGAUAGAAAUUCGUGAGAUGGAGACCCCAGAUUGGACCCCAGACAUUAAGCACAGCAAGAUAUGGUUUGGAAGCAACAUGGGAAAUGGAACUGUUUUUCUUGGCAUACCAGGAGACAAUAAACAAGUUGUUUCAGAAGGAUUCUAUUUCUAUAUGUUGAAAUGUGCUGAAGAUGAUACUAAUGAAGAGCAGACAACAUUCACAAACAGUCAAACAUCAACAGAAGAUCCAGGGGAUUCCACUCCCUUUGAAGACUCUGAAGAAUUUUGUUUCAGUGCAGAAGCAAAUAGUUUUGAUGGUGAUGAUGAAUUUGACACCUAUAAUGAAGAUGAUGAAGAAGAUGAGUCUGAGACAGGCUACUGGAUUACAUGCUGCCCUACUUGUGAUGUGGAUAUCAACACUUGGGUACCAUUCUAUUCAACUGAGCUCAACAAACCCGCCAUGAUCUACUGCUCUCAUGGGGAUGGGCACUGGGUCCAUGCUCAGUGCAUGGAUCUGGCAGAACGCACACUCAUCCAUCUGUCAGCAGGAAGCAACAAGUAUUACUGCAAUGAGCAUGUGGAGAUAGCAAGAGCUCUACACACUCCCCAAAGAGUCCUACCCUUAAAAAAGCCUCCAAUGAAAUCCCUCCGUAAAAAAGGUUCUGGAAAAAUCUUGACUCCUGCCAAGAAAUCCUUUCUUAGAAGGUUGUUUGAUUAGUUUUGCAAAAGCCUUUCAGAUUCAGGUGUAUGGAAUUUUUGAAUCUAUUUUUAAAAUCAUAACAUUGAUUUUAAAAAUACAUUUUUGUUUAUUUAAAAUGCCUAUGUUUUCUUUUAGUUACAUGAAUUAAGGGCCAGAAAAAAGUGUUUAUAAUGCAAUGAUAAAUAAAGUCAUUCUAGACCCUAUACAUUUUGAAAAUAUUUUACCCAAAUACUCAAUUUACUAAUUUAUUCUUCACUGAGGAUUUCUGAUCUGAUUUUUUAUUCAACAAACCUUAAACACCCAGAAGCAGUAAUAAUCAUCGAGGUAUGUUUAUAUUUAUUAUAUAAGUCUUGGUAACAAAUAACCUAUAAAGUGUUUAUGACAAAUUUAGCCAAUAAAGAAAUUAACACCCAAAAGAAUUAAAUUGAUUAUUUUGUGCAACAUAACAAUUCGGCAGUUGGCCAAAACUUAAAAGCAAGAUCUACUACAUCCCACAUUAGUGUUCUUUAUAUACCUUCAAGCAACCCUUUGGAUUAUGCCCAUGAACAAGUUAGUUUCUCAUAGCUUUACAGAUGUAGAUAUAAAUAUAAAUAUAUGUAUACAUAUAGAUAGAUAAUGUUCUCCACUGACACAAAAGAAGAAAUAAAUAAUCUACAUCAA